UCACCCCAGACCUGCUGAUGACCCCCAGUGACCAGGGCGAUGUCGACCUGGAUGUGGACUUUGCUGCACACCGGGGGAACUGGACAGGCAAGCUGGACUUCCUGCUGUCCUGCAUUGGCUACUGUGUAGGCCUGGGGAAUGUCUGGCGCUUCCCCUAUCGAGCGUACACCAAUGGAGGAGGUAUGGGCCUGAGGUCCUGUCGGAGGGUGUCUGGGGUGAUGGGCCAAGGCCCUGGGGUACAGUGAGCUUUUAGGUGGCCUCAGCCACUGUCUCCUAGGCGACCUUGGGCAGAACUCAUUGAAAGUGGUUUAUAGUAACUUGGGGCUGGGAGGAAGGAGUUUACCCUGUCUUGUCCUUCUCAUCACCCAAGCCCUUCCUUCCUCCCUCUCAUCCCCAGGAAGGAUACCCACAUGGUUCCCUCUCUAAGGCUGGCCACCCCACGCCCUGCACGGUGGGCAGAGGGAGCUGCCUCUGCUUCGUGAUAAGGAGCUGUAUCUGCCUGCCGAUGAUCACUGCACUUUCAGUGUUCUCCCCACCCCCUCCUUCCUCCACCUCCUCCUGAGCUGUGCUCCAUCAAUCAUUCCCUCUCUUGAGUCUCCAAUCUUUCCUCCUCUCUUGGUUCCUUCCAUUCAGGCUGCAAACACAAAGUCUCUCCCAUCUUAAACAAAUUUCCUUUCAUCCCUGCUUCUCCAUCAAGUGACGGUUCCAAGUCUCAUUAGCAAAAGCUGGGGCUGAGCGCCUACCACCUGUCAGGCCCUGGGCUUGGUGCUUGCUGUGCCCAUCUCAUUUAACCCUGGUGAUGACCCUAUUGGGUAGGCACCAUGGAUACGAUGAGGUAGCUGAAACUUGAAGACACCAGCGUCCUUGCCCAAGGUCACAGGGUGGCAGACCCAACAUUCCAACCCAGGACUAUCUCCUCCCUAGCCAGUGUGCUCUCACCAGUACUCGUAUCUCCUUCUGUCUCUAGCAAACUCUGAAGGAAGCAUAUAUUGAGAAAGUGAGAGAAAUCCAAAUAAAGCUAGAUGAAGCAAAGAAAGGAUAAAUUUACAUGACUAGGAUGUGUGGGACUGGAGCUGGCCUCUGAAGCUCUAGGACCUUGAUGACACCCAUGGUGUCUCUCGGCAAGCACUCUCCCCAUGUCCCUACUCUUCCUCUCUGUGUGCUGACCUCAUUUUGUCCUGAGACAGGCUUCCUCCCCGCAGUUGGUGGGGGACAGGCCUUGGGGGGAGGUGGCCACAGACAACUCUGCAAUGACUUCAUCCUCCAAUGGGUUUAGCAACCCAAGAGCUUUGCAGAACUGCUCUGUCUGAAUGAAUCUAUACAGAAUUGCAGGGAAGGCCUCUGAUAGGCCUGGCUUUGGAUAGGUGCCCACGGGGGAAGGAGGAGAGGGCGGUGAACCCCCUCCUUCCAGCCCCAGGUUAUGAUAAAACACUUCCAACUAAUUCUGCCCAAGGUCGCCUAGGAGGGGGUUGGUUGAUGUGACUGGCAGCCCUUCCAGAGUCAUAUGGUGGUGGGCAGUUCUCUAAAGAAGUGACUGCCAAUGUGAGAACCAAAGGGGAAGGGCUAUUGGGCCCACGGAACCACAGGUGGCAGUCACAAGUGUCUGAGGCGGCAUGGUGGGGAGGGGCAGGCAGAUAGAGGGGAGCCGGAUUCUGAAGGGUGCUGGUUUCUGUACUGAGGAGUCUGCACUUUCUUCAGCAGGAAAUUCACACAUUCUCUCCCUCAUUCAUUCAUUCACUCCCUCAGCAGGCGUUUCUCAGCGUCUGCGCUGAGCCCAGCACUGUUCUGGGCACUGGGGCUCCAGAGGCGCCUUCCUCGUGCCCUACUUCCUCAUGCUGGCCAUCUGUGGCAUCCCCCUCUUCUUCCUGGAGCUCUCCCUGGGCCAGUUCUCCAGCCUAGGGCCCCUGGCUGUCUGGAAAAUCAGCCCUCUCUUCAAAGGCGCCGGCGCAGCCAUGCUGCUCAUCGUGGGCUUGGUGGCCAUCUACUACAACAUGAUCAUCGCCUACGUGCUCUUCUACCUCUUCGCCUCCCUCACCAGCGACCUACCCUGGGAGCACUGUGGCAACUGGUGGAACACAGAACUCUGCCUGGAGCACAGAGUCUCCAAGGACGGCAACGGGGCCCUGCCCCUCAACCUCACCUGCACCGUCAGCCCCAGCGAGGAGUACUGGAGCCAAACCCACACGGAAGCUGAAGAGGAAGGAAGAAGAGGAAGGGUGGUCUCGAACUCCUAUCCUCAAGUGAUCUUCCUUCCUCAGCCUCCCAAAGCUGAGGAAGGGGUAAGCCGCUACGUCCUCCACAUCCAAGGCAGCCAGGGCAUCGGCAGCCCUGGGGAGAUCCGCUGGAACCUCUGCCUCUGCCUGCUGCUGGCCUGGGUCAUCGUGUUCCUCUGUAUCCUCAAGGGUGUGAAGUCUUCGGGCAAGGUGGUGUAUUUCACGGCCACGUUCCCCUACCUCAUCCUGCUCAUGCUGCUGGUCCGCGGAGUCACCCUCCCAGGGGCCUGGAAGGGCAUCCAGUUCUAUCUCACCCCCCAGUUCCACCACUUGUUGUCUUCCAAGGUGUGGAUUGAAGCUGCUCUUCAGAUCUUCUAUUCCCUGGGUGUGGGCUUCGGGGGGCUCCUCACCUUUGCCUCCUACAACACGUUUCACCAGAACAUCUAUAGAGACACUUUCAUCGUCACUCUGGGCAACGCCAUCACCAGCAUCCUGGCUGGCUUUGCCAUCUUCUCCGUGCUGGGCUACAUGUCUCAGGAGCUGGGCGUGCCUGUGGACCAAGUAGCCAAAGCAGGCCCUGGCCUGGCCUUUGUCGUCUACCCACAGGCCAUGACCAUGCUGCCUCUGUCACCCUUCUGGUCCUUUCUCUUCUUCUUCAUGCUUCUGACUCUCGGCCUAGAUAGCCAGUUUGCUUUUCUGGAGACCAUUGUGACAGCUGUGACAGAUGAGUUCCCAUACUACCUGCGGCCCAAGAAGGCGGUGUUCUCAGGGCUCAUCUGCGUGGCCAUGUACCUGAUGGGGCUGAUCCUCACCACUGAUGGGGGCAUGUACUGGCUGGUCCUUCUGGAUGACUACAGCGCCAGCUUCGGGCUGAUGGUGGUGGUUAUCACCACGUGCCUUGCCGUGACACGGGUGUAUGGCAUUCAGAGGUUCUGCCGAGACAUCCACAUGAUGCUGGGCUUCAAGCCGGGCCUCUACUUCAGGGCCUGCUGGCUGUUCCUGUCCCCAGCCACGCUCUUGGCCCUCAUGGUGUAUAGCAUCGUCAAGUACCAGCCCUCGGAGUAUGGCAGUUACCGCUUCCCGCCCUGGGCUGAGCUGCUGGGCAUCCUGAUGGGCCUGCUGUCCUGCCUCAUGAUCCCAGCUGGCAUGCUGGUGGCUGUGCUUCGAGAAGAGGGCUCACUCUGGGAGCGGCUCCAACAGGCCAGCCGGCCGGCCAUGGACUGGGGACCAUCGCUGGAGGAGAACCGGACGGGCAUGUAUGUGGCCACGCUGGCUGGGAGCCAGUCACCAAAGCCACUGAUGGUGCACAUGCGCAAGUACGGGGGCAUCACCAGCUUCGAGAACACGGCCAUCGAGGUGGACCGUGAGAUUGCAGAGGAGGAGGAGUCGAUGAUGUGAGGCAGGAGGCAGGCGGGCAGAAGGCCCUGCCCGGGACCUCACAGUCCCUUCUUAGAAGCCUGCAAAGGUCAGCUGUGCCCUCUGGGAUUCUGAGAGGCUAUGGGGGGGCCUGCCAUAGGGAUGCCAGUCCCCCAGUGGGGGUCCCUUCUGCAGCCUCUGCCUCUCCUGAAACCUCUGACAACCCCCUACACACACACACAGGCAUACUCAGACCCACUCAAAGCUGAGAAUGAUCCAACUCAGCCCUACUUUGCGGAUGGACAUAUUAAGGCCAGGAGGGGAGGGACUUGCCCCAGGUCGCAUGGCAGAGGGGACUUGAACCCACGCCUCCUGACCAGCCAGCUCCCUUUCCCAUGGGGCAGCCGGCACCACCUUCUCAUCUCUAUUCAGGGCCUACACCCCUCCCUUUUUGGGGGGAGCCUGUCCCCACACACCUUAGCACAACCAGAAUCUUGAGUUGGGCAGGGAAGGUCAGGGCUACAGAGGCUCUUGAGGCUCCGAGGCCCUGGGGAUCAAAGGUCAAUGAGUUAGGUGGGGAGAAAGAUCCCUGGGGGCUCCUGUAUGCAGGACUCCUGAAGGAGGUGGGAGCUGAGGGCCCUGGAGGAUGGGGAAGGUUUGCAGAGAGAGGAAGAAGAGGGCAGGGUGGGGAGGAGCUCUGGGCCAGAGGAUGCUGAGCUGCCUGGGCAGAGACCAAGAGGGUUGGAGACACUAGUUUUACCAGGUUACAGGAGGGUUCAAGACAGAAGGAAAACUAACAGAGGGGGAGCCAGGGAUGAUGGGGUGGGCAGGGGAUUUGCAUGAUGAGGAGUAUCAUUCCAGAUCUGUGCAGAGCGGAUCGGACGGGACAGGGUGGAGCGGGGAGGCCUGUGCAAAGUGGGAAAGAGCUGCCGGUGGCCUGAGCCAGGGUGCUGGGGCUGCGGGUGGGGAAAGGAGGCCCCAGCACUUCAGACAAAGACCACCCCUUCACCCACUGGACCCCAAGCCGCAAAAGCUGGGGAGGUAGGAAGGGUCACUGUGAGGGCCCAGGGCCCCUCUCUUCCCAUCUCCCUUGUCCUGGUGGCCUUCAGUGUCUCUUCCAGUUCCAGGAGCUGCUGGGAAGCUGGCCUUCAUUGUUGGUGACAGGGCAACCAUGGGACUAGGAGGUGGCCCAUACACAUGGCUGGCUGGUCCUGAGGCCACCCACCUUGUUCCAGGACAUGGGCCCGGGCCCGGUGUGGGGGUAGACGCAGAGGGCAGAGGGUAGCCCUUGGUACUGUGGGUCCCUCAAAGAGGAGAGUGGGGUGCAGAAAUGCCUCAGCAUGGCUCAUGCACACAGCAUUCUCCCGUGGGGCAGGGUUCCCUCAUGCAACAGGCCUCCCUGUGGCCAGCCUCUCUGCCUGUCUCUCGCUGCGUCCCCCCAACCCCUUGUGUUCUAUUGGUUCAUUGUUAAUAAAUAUCAAAUGAGGUCA